AGGCCCGGCCCCUGCGGAGCCCAGAGACGCGGGGACACAGGUGAGGCGCGCGGGGUCCGGGCUGCGGCUUCCCGGUGCGGCCGCAGUGGGCAGGUGCGACUGUGCGCGGCCUCGCUGGCUGAGAACUGGCGGGGGUGGGGGCGUGCCCUGGACUGACCCCCACCGGCCUAACCCGCGGUGCGGGGCCAGGGCCGGAACUGCCCGCCCGGCUCCUUGCCCGGCUCCUUGUGGCUGCUGGGGACCCCCGACACCAGCCACUUUCCCUUCCCGGCCCUUAGCAAGAUCGGCUUCUCCGGUCACCUUUAUUUUUUUAGGCUCGAGGCGUCUGCCGCACCUCAGCCCACGACCUGCCCCGCUGGGAGGUGCGGGCCGCUGGCCAGGCCCUGACCGCAACCUGGCCCAGAGGCCCCAGCCCUCAGGCAAGGUUCUCCGGUGAAGCCACAGCCUGGCCACCUGUCUUGAUCUCCCCACCGAGAAGGCCCCGCCCCUCCCGCUGCAGCCCCACAGCAUGCAGCCCCAGGAGAGCCACGUCCACUAUAGUAGGUGGGAGGACGGCAGCAGGGACGGAGUCAGCCUAGGGGCUGUGUCCAGCACAGAAGAGGCCUCACGCUGCCGCAGGAUCUCCCAGAGGCUGUGCACGGGCAAGCUGGGCAUCGCCAUGAAGGUGCUGGGCGGCGUGGCCCUCUUCUGGAUCAUCUUCAUCCUGGGCUACCUCACAGGCUACUAUGUGCACAAGUGCAAAUAAAUGCUGCCCCGCAUGCACGCGGGGGGCUGGCCGCA